AGCCCCGGGGCCGCGCCGCAGAGUCGGGCUUCCUGGAUACAUAGAGGCUUGUGCCAGGCGGGGUGGGAAGACUGGAUUUUGCAGUGGAAGCAGCAUCUCUUCCGUCUGGGACCUGGCUGAGGGCGUCCCCACCCUGGGGGGAGCAGAGGACCAGCCCUGACCUAGCCGGGCCCAGCCUCGUCCUGCCCGGCCUGAGCGCCCCGCCCAGCAGCCGGCUCUGGCCCACCGGGGUCCGGGAGCGCGGGCGCCAUGGACAAGAUCUUGGAGGCGGUGGUGACGUCGUCAUACCCGGUCAGCGUGAAGCAGGGGCUGGUUCGGCGCGUGCUGGAGGCGGCGCGGCAGCCGCUGGAGCGUGAGCAGUGCCUGGCGCUGCUGGCGCUGGGCGCGCGCCUCUACGUGGGCGGCGCGGAGGAGCUGCCGCGCCGCGUGGGCUGCCAGCUGCUGCACGUGGCCGGCCGCCACCACCCCGACGUCUUCGCCGAGUUCUUCAGCGCGCGUCGCGUGCUGCGCCUGCUGCAGGGUGGCGCCGGCCCCCCGGGCCCCCGCGCGCUCGCCUGCGUGCAGCUGGGUCUGCAGCUGCUGCCCGAGGGGCCUGCGGCCGACGAGGUGUUCGCGCUGCUGCGGCGCGAGGUGCUGCGCACCGUGUGCGAGCGCCCGGGCCCCGCGGCCUGCGCGCAGGUGGCACGGCUGCUGGCUCGCCACCCGCGCUGUGUGCCCGACGGACCCCACCGCCUGCUCUUCUGCCAGCAGCUGGUGCGUUGCCUCGGCCGCUUCCGCUGCCCAGCCGAAGGCGAGGAGGGCGCCGUGGAGUUCCUAGAGCAGGCCCAGCAGGUGAGCGGGCUCCUGGCGCAGCUGUGGCGCGCACAGCCCGCCGCCAUCCUGCCCUGCCUCAAAGAGCUGUUCGCAGUCAUCUCCUGCGCAGAGGAGGAGCCACCAUCUAGCGCCCUGGCCAGCGUGGUCCAGCACCUCCCAUUGGAGCUCAUGGAUGGUGUUGUCCGGAACCUCAGCAAUGAUGACAGUGUGACAGACUCGCAGAUGCUGACUGCCAUUAGCAGGAUGAUUGACUGGGUGUCCUGGCCCCUGGGGAAGAAUAUUGACAAGUGGAUCAUUGCACUGCUGAAGGGCCUGGCUGCUGUUAAGAAGUUCAGCAUCUUGAUCGAGGUUUCGCUCACCAAAAUUGAGAAGGUUUUCUCUAAGCUGCUGUACCCCAUCGUCCGGGGAGCUGCCUUGUCUGUGCUCAAGUACAUGCUCCUGACCUUCCAGCACUCCCACGAAGCCUUCCACCUGCUCCUCCCUCACAUCCCCCCCAUGGUGGCCUCUCUGGUCAAGGAGGACUCGAACUCGGGGACCAGCUGCCUGGAGCAGCUGGCGGAGCUGGUCCACUGCAUGGUGUUCCGGUUCCCGGGCUUCCCGGAUCUGUAUGAGCCUGUCAUGGAGGCCAUCAAGGACCUCCAUGUUCCCAAUGAGGACCGCAUCAAGCAGCUGCUGGGGCAGGAUGCCUGGACUUCGCAGAAGAGCGAGCUGGCGGGUUUCUAUCCCCGGCUCAUGGCCAAGUCAGACACGGGCAAGAUUGGUCUCAUCAACCUGGGCAACACAUGCUAUGUCAACAGCAUCCUUCAGGCCUUAUUCAUGGCGUCUGACUUCAGACAUUGUGUGCUCCGCUUGACUGAGAACAACUCACAGCCCCUGAUGACCAAGCUGCAGUGGCUCUUUGGCUUCCUAGAACACAGCCAGCGGCCUGCCAUUUCCCCAGAGAACUUCCUCUCCGCAUCCUGGACGCCCUGGUUCAGCCCUGGCACCCAGCAGGACUGCUCGGAGUAUCUGAAGUACCUGCUGGAUCGGCUGCACGAAGAGGAGAAAACGGGCACAAGGAUCUGCCAGAAACUCAAGCAGUCCAGCUCGCCCUCUCCGCCCGAGGAGCCCCCGGCCCCAAGUUCAACCUCUGUGGAAAAAAUGUUUGGAGGCAAGAUAGUGACUCGGAUCUGCUGUCUCUGCUGCCUCAACGUCUCCUCCCGGGAGGAGGCCUUCACGGACCUCUCUCUCGCCUUCCCUCCUCCUGAGCGCUGUCGCCGCCGCCGCCUGGGCUCUGUGAUGCGCCCCACAGAAGACAUCACAGCCCGGGAGUUGCCCCCACCAACCAGUGCACAGGGGCCAGGCAGGGUGGGUCCUCGGAGGCAAAGGAAACACUGCAUCACAGAGGACACCCCCCCCACCAGCCUGUACAUCGAAGGCCUGGACUCCAAGGAAGCUGGUGGGCAGAGCAGUCAGGAGGAAAGGAUAGAGAGGGAGGAAGAAGGGAAGGAGGAGAGAACGGAGAAGGAAGAAGUGGGGGAGGAGGAGGAAAGCACCAGAGGGGAAGGAGAGAGGGAGAAAGAGGAGGAGGUGGAAGAGGAAGAAGAGAAGGUGGAGAAGGAGACAGAAAAGGAGGCUGAGCAGGAAAAGGAAGAAGACAGCCUGGGAGCGGGGACCCACCCGGAUGCUGCCAUCCCCUCCGGGGAGCGGACAUGUGGCUCUGAGGGCUCCCGCUCCGUCCUGGACCUGGUUAACUACUUCCUGUCCCCCGAGAAGCUGACAGCAGAAAACCGCUACUACUGCGAGUCGUGUGCCUCCCUGCAGGAUGCCGAGAAGGUGGUGGAGCUGAGCCAAGGGCCGUGCUACCUCAUCCUCACACUGCUGCGCUUCUCUUUCGACCUGCGCACCAUGCGGCGCCGCAAGAUCCUGGAUGACGUCUCCAUCCCCCUGCUGCUCCGCCUGCCACUGGCUGGUGGCCGUGGCCAGGCCUAUGACCUCUGCAGUGUGGUGGUGCACUCUGGAGUGUCUUCGGAGAGUGGUCACUACUACUGCUAUGCCCGUGAGGGCGCUGCCCGCCCUGCCGCUUCUCUGGGAACUGCCGAUAGGCCAGAGCCCGAGAACCAGUGGUACCUGUUCAAUGACACUCGGGUGUCCUUCUCUUCCUUCGAAUCUGUCAGCAACGUCACCUCCUUCUUCCCUAAGGACACAGCCUAUGUGCUGUUUUACCGGCAGCGGCCCAGGGAGGGGCCCGAGGCUGAGUUGGGCUCUUCUAGAGUCCGGACAGAGCCCACCCUGCACAAGGACUUGAUGGAAGCCAUUUCCAAAGACAACAUCCUUUACCUACAGGAGCAGGAGAAGGAGGCCCGGAGCAGGGCGGCCUACAUCUCUGCACUCCCCACAUCUCCGCACUGGGGGAGGGGCUUUGAUGAAGACAAGGAUGAGGAUGAAGGCUCUCCAGGGGGCUGCAAUCCUGCAGGUGGCAAUGGUGGUGACUUCCACAGACUGGUCUUCUAAUGUGAACCUGCUGCCAACCUGACCCCUUCCCUCCAGGAGCCAGGUUUAACAGCCUUCUUGAAAUAAGAAGACAGACACUGGCUAGAAUCUGGAAUGAGGCCCCAAAGGCUGGAGGACAAAAAUAAGUCCAGUGAAACCAACUUGUCUUCAAAGAGAAAAAGAACUCUAUUUGUCUUGACUCUGCCAGUUCAAAACUCUUUCCGUUGGCAAUAGAUAUUAUUCUGAAUAGUUACUUAUUUUAGCUCAGUGGAAGACCUGCAUUUUGAGAAAUGAAGUUAUUUUAGCAAGAAUACAUAUUAUCUAGUACUUGAAGGAAGACUAGUGGCUAUUAUUGCAGUAAAAGUGAUGAUAAAUACAUAAUUCACAGUUUUAUUUCUAAGGUGCUUAAUUUACUGUAUCUUUACAAUCAGGUUCCCACAUAAAUGAAAAAAGAGAUAGAUAGAAGGCUGGUAUUAGUAGCCUCAGUAAUCCAAUCAGACACAGUUAUGUCUAGUCUAUGCGAGGCAGGAUGAAUGGGCUGAUUCACUUUAUACCCCCUACUCAAAAAUAAUCUUACAGGAUUACUUUGGAGAUCAUAUGAGGUACCUAAUGUAAAAGUGCUUUGUAAACUUUAAAGCAUCAUUUCUUUCUUCCAGAGCACCUAGUAUAUAAUGUGAAUGUUAGAGGAAACACAGGAUUAAAGUCUAUUCAUAUACUUACCAAUACCUGGCACUGUUAAGUUUUUUUUUUUUUUUUGGUGACAAGGUCUGGCUCUAUUGCCCAGGCUGGAAUGCAGUGACGUGAUCUCAGCUCACUGCAACCUCCGCCUCCUGGGCUCAAGCCAUCCUCCCACCUCAGUCUUCUGAGUAGCUGGGGCUACAGGCAUGUGCCACCAUGCCUGGCUAAUUGUUUUUGGUAGAGAUGGGGUGUCGCCAUGUUGCCCGGGCUGGUCUCAAACUUGUGAGCUGAAGCAAUCCGCCUGUCUUGGUCUCCCAAAGUGCUGGGAUUAUAGGCAUGAGCCACUGCGUCUGGCCUGUUAGCCAUUUUUAUUUUAGCCCUUCCAGCAGAGGUAAAGCAGAAUCUCACUGAGAUUUUAAUUUGCAUUUCCCAGAUCACUGAUCAUCUAUUCAUGUGGUUACUGGACAUUCCUAUAUCUUUUUUUGUUGAAGAAUCUAUUCACAUUUUUUGCCCAUUAAAAAAAUAUUGGAUUGCUCUCUUCUUACUGAGUUGUAGAAGUUCUUUAUAUGGACCACAAACAAAUCCUUUGUUAGAUAUGCGCGUUGAAUAUUUUCUCGCAUUUUGUGAUUUGUCUUUUUUUUUGAGAUGGAGUCUUGCUCACUCUGUCGCCCAAGCUAGAGUGCAGUGGUGCCAUCUUGGCUCACUGCAACCUCCACCUCCUGGGUUCAAGCGAUUCUCCAGCCUCAGCCUCGCCAGUAGCUGGCACUAUAGAUGAGCACAUCCACGCCUGUCUAAUUUUUGUAUUUUUAGCAGAGGUUUAGCAUGGGGCUUCACCAUAUUGGCCAGGCUGGUCUCGAACUCCUGGCCUCAAGUUAUCUGCCUGCUGCCUCCCAAAGUGCUGAGAUUACAGGCGUGGGCCACCACGCCCAGCCCAUUUUCUUUUCUUAAAGAGGCCUCUUGAAGAACUAGUUUUAAUUUUGAUAAAGACUACUUCACCAAAAACUACAGUUUUUUCUCUUUUAUGAUUCUUGCUUUUUCUGUCCUAUAUAAAAAUCUUUGCUUACCUCAAGAUCAUGGAGAUGUUUUCUUCUAGAAGUUUCUUUUCUUUUCUUUUUAUUUAAAUACAGGGUCUUAUUCUGUCGCCCAGGCUGGAGUGCAAUGGAAUGAUCUUGGCUCACUGCAGUCUUGACCUCCCCCAGGCUCAAGUGAUCCUCCCACCACAGCCUGCUGAGUAGCUGGGAAUGCAAGCACAUGUGACCGUGCCUGGCUACUUUUUGUAUUUUCUGUAGAGACUGGGUUUUGCCAUGUUAUCCAGGCUGGUUUUCAACUCCUGAGCUCAAGCAAUCUGCCCUUCUUAGUCUUCCAAAGUGCUGGGAUUACAGGCGUGAACUACUGCGCCCAGCCUAGAAGUUUCGUAGUAUUAGAUUUUACAUUUAUGUCUCUGAUACAUUUUAAUUUUUGGGUGAGUGGUGUGAUAUGAAGGGUUGCUGUUCUUUUUUUAUUAUUCCUAUAUGAAUGUCAAGCUGUUUCAGCAUCAUUUGCAGAACAGGUUUUUCCUUUCUCCAUUGGCAUCUAUAUAUUUAUAUACUUUUAAUAAUUAUAUAUAUUUAUAUAUUUAAACUAUUUUUAUUUAUAUAUGCAUUUAAAAUAUUUAUAUACAUAUAUGUAUUUAUAUAUAUUUCUCUCCUGGACUUGCUAAUUCUUCUAGUGAUCUACAGGUUUUUGUCCUUUCACCAAUACAACAUUAUCUUGAUUACCAUAGUUUGACAGGAAUUCUUGAAAUCAAGUAAUAUAAAUCCUGACUUUAUUGUUGUUCUUUUAAAAAUUUCUUUGGUUGCUUGGCCAACAUGGUGAAACCCCACCUCUACUAAAAAUACAAAAAUUAGCCAAGCAUGGUGGCACGCGCCUGUAAUCCCAGCUACUCAGGAGGCUGAGGCAGGAGAAUUGCUUGAACCCAGGAGGCGAAGGUUGCAAUGAGCUGAGAUCAUGCCACUGCAUUCCAGCCCGGGAGACAGAGCGACAGACUUUCUCCUCCCGGGCCACCGGGAGGGGCUGCCAUGAAGGUCUCUGAUGUGGCCUGGAGACAUUUUCCCCAUGGUCUUGGAGAUUAACAUUAGGCUCCUUGCUACUUAUGCAAAUUUCUACAGCCGGUUUGAUUUUCUCCCCAGAAAAUGGGUUUUUCUUUUCUUUUUGAGACAGAGUCUCACUCUGUCGCCCAGGCUGGAGUGCAGUGGCACGAUCUCGGCUCACUGCAAGCUCCGCCUCCCGGGUUCACGCCAUUCUCCUGCCUCAGUCUCCCGAGUAGCUGGGACUAAAGGCGCCCGUCACCAUGCCGGGCUAAUUUUUUGUAUUUUGAGUAGAGAUGGGGUUUCACCGUGUUAGCCAGGAUGGUCUCGAUCUCCUGACCUUGAGAUCCGCCCACCUCAGCCUCCCAAAGUGCUUGGAUUACAGGCUUGAGCCACUGCGCCCGGCUGGGUGUUUCUUUUCUAUCACAUCGUCAGGUGGCAAAUUUUCCGAACAUUUAUGCUCUGCUUUCCCUUAUAAAAUUGAAUGCCUUUAACGAUACCCAAGUCACCUCUUGAAUGCUUUGCUGCUUAGAAAUUUCUUCCGCCAGAUACCCUAAAUCAUCUCUCUCAAGUUCAAAGUUCCACAAAUCUCUAGGGCAGGGGCAAAAUGCCACCAGUCUCUGCUAAAACAACAAGAGUCACCUUUGCUCCAGUUGCCAACAAGUUCCUCAUCUCCAUCUGAGACCACCUUAGCCUGGACCUUAUUGUCCAUAUCGCUAUCAGGCUUUUGGUCACAGCCAUUCCACAAGUCUCUAGGAAGUUCCAGACUUUCCCACAUUUUCCUGUCUUCUUCUGAGCCCUCCAAACUGUUCCAACCUCUGCCUGUUACCCAGUUCCAAAGUCGCUUCCACAUUUUUGGUAUCUUUUCAGCAACGCCCCACUCUACUGGUACCAAUUAACUGUAUUAGUCCAUUUUCAUGCUGCUGAUAAAGACAUACCCGAGACUGGGAUUUUUAUUUGGAUUGUGUUGAAUCUACAGAACAAUUUGAGAAAAACUGCCAUCUAAAUAAUAAUAGGUCUUCUAGUUCAUAACUACUGUACAUCACUCUCCAUAUUUAGGUCUUUAAUUUCUACCAGCAACAUUUGAUAGUUUUCAGUGAAGAGGUGUUGCAUGUUUGUUGUUAAAUUUAUUCCCAAGUAUUCCACGUUUUCUGGUACCAUUCGAUAUAUAAUUAAAAUUUUUUCAUUUUCCAAUUGUUCACUGCAUACUGUAAAACUUAUUUUUUGCAUAAAAACCUUUUUAUCUUGUGACCUUGCUAAACUCACUUAAAAAUUUUUUUGUUGUUAAAAUACACAGGGUUUCGCCAUGUUGCUCAGGCUGGUCUCGAACUCUUGAGCUCCAGGUAUCCACCUGCCUCAGCAUCCUAAAGUGCUGGGAUUACAGGCAUGAACCACCACACCAGGACUCUUAUUUAUUUUUCUUCCUCCAUGGAACUGAUGAGAAUCUCCAGUACAAUGUUAAAUAGAAGUGGUAAGAACAGGUACUUUCUCCUUGUUUUCAAUCUUAGGGCAUUAUGUUCAAUAUUUCUCCAUUAGGUAUGAUCUUAGCUAUAGGGUUCCUUAGAAGUCCUUUAUCAGUUUAAAGAAGUUCUCCUCAAUUCAUAGUUUGCUAAGAAAUACUUUUUUUUCAAUGAAGUACUGAGUUGUCAAAUGCUUCCUCUGCAUCUAUUGAGGUUAUGAUUAUAUUAUUUUUCUCCUUCAUUCUCUUAAUGUAAUGAAUUACUUUGAUUGUUUUUUUUUUGAAGUCAAACCAACCUUACACUCCUGGGAUAAACACUACUUUGUCAUGAUGUCUUACCCCUAAUGUAUACACACAUGCAUAUUCCCUAAAAUAUAUAUAUUGUCCCAAACAGACACAUAUAGAUAUACACACAUACGUAUUUAGUUGGAUUCGACUGCUAAUCCUUUGUUUUUAAAGAGGAUUUCUGUUUAUUAUUCAUGGGGGAUAUUCUCUGUAAUUUUAUUUCCUGUCAUCUUUGCCAGAUUUUGAUAGUAGGGUUAUGCUGGUCUCAUAAAAUGAGCUGUGAAAGAAUCCCCUCCUCCUAUGUUUUCUGAAAGACUGUGGGUAAGAUUGGUGUUAUCUUUGAAUGCUUGGUAGAAUUUACCAGUAAAACCAUCUGGGCAUAGUUUUCUAGGUAUUUGUCCAAGAGAAAUAAAAACAAAUGUUUCUACAAA